ACUGAGCAGCGCCAUGGAGGACUCUGAAGCACUGGGCUUCGAACACAUGGGCCUCGAUCCCCGGCUCCUUCAGGCUGUCACCGAUCUGGGCUGGUCGCGACCUACGCUGAUCCAGGAGAAGGCCAUCCCACUGGCCCUAGAAGGGAAGGACCUCCUGGCUCGGGCCCGCACGGGCUCCGGGAAGACGGCCGCUUAUGCUAUUCCGAUGCUGCAGCUGUUGCUCCAUAGGAAGGCGACAGGUCCGGUGGUAGAACAGGCAGUGAGAGGCCUUGUUCUUGUUCCUACCAAGGAGCUGGCACGGCAAGCACAGUCCAUGAUUCAGCAGCUGGCUACCUACUGUGCUCGGGAUGUCCGAGUGGCCAAUGUCUCAGCUGCUGAAGACUCAGUCUCUCAGAGAGCUGUGCUGAUGGAGAAGCCAGAUGUGGUAGUAGGGACCCCAUCUCGCAUAUUAAGCCACUUGCAGCAAGACAGCCUGAAACUUCGUGACUCCCUGGAGCUUUUGGUGGUGGACGAAGCUGACCUUCUUUUUUCCUUUGGCUUUGAAGAAGAGCUCAAGAGUCUCCUCUGUCACUUGCCCCGGAUUUACCAGGCUUUUCUCAUGUCAGCUACUUUUAACGAGGACGUACAAGCACUCAAGGAGCUGAUAUUACAUAACCCGGUUACCCUUAAGUUACAGGAGUCCCAGCUGCCUGGGCCAGACCAGUUACAGCAGUUUCAGGUGGUCUGUGAGACUGAGGAAGACAAAUUCCUCCUGCUGUAUGCCCUGCUCAAGCUGUCAUUGAUUCGGGGCAAGUCUCUGCUCUUUGUCAACACUCUAGAACGGAGUUACCGGCUACGCCUGUUCUUGGAACAGUUCAGCAUCCCCACCUGUGUGCUCAAUGGAGAGCUUCCACUGCGCUCCAGGUGCCACAUCAUCUCACAGUUCAACCAAGGCUUCUACGACUGUGUCAUAGCAACUGAUGCUGAAGUCCUGGGGGCCCCAGUCAAGGGCAAGCGUCGGGGCCGAGGGCCCAAAGGGGACAAGGCCUCUGAUCCGGAAGCAGGUGUGGCCCGGGGCAUAGACUUCCACCAUGUGUCUGCUGUGCUCAACUUUGAUCUUCCCCCAACCCCUGAGGCCUACAUCCAUCGAGCUGGCAGGACAGCACGCGCUAACAACCCAGGCAUAGUCUUAACCUUUGUGCUUCCCACGGAGCAGUUCCACUUAGGCAAGAUUGAGGAGCUUCUCAGUGGAGAGAACAGGGGCCCCAUUCUGCUCCCCUACCAGUUCCGGAUGGAGGAGAUCGAGGGCUUCCGCUAUCGCUGCAGGGAUGCCAUGCGCUCAGUGACUAAGCAGGCCAUUCGGGAGGCAAGAUUGAAGGAGAUCAAGGAAGAGCUUCUGCAUUCUGAGAAGCUUAAGACAUACUUUGAAGACAACCCUAGGGACCUCCAGCUGCUGCGGCAUGACCUACCUUUGCACCCCGCAGUGGUGAAGCCCCACCUGGGCCAUGUUCCUGACUACCUGGUUCCUCCUGCUCUCCGUGGCCUGGUGCGCCCUCACAAGAAGCGGAAGAAGCUGUCUUCCUCUUGUAGGAAGGCCAAGAGAGCAAAGUCCCAGAACCCACUGCGCAGCUUCAAGCACAAAGGAAAGAAAUUCAGACCCACAGCCAAGCCCUCCUGAGGUUGUUGGGCCUCUCUGGAGCUGAGCACAUUGUGGAGCACAGGCUUACACCCUUCGUGGACAGGCGAGGCUCUGGUGCUUACUGCACAGCCUGAACAGACAGUUCUGGGGCCGGCAGUGCUGGGCCCUUUAGCUCCUUGGCACUUCCAAGCUGGCAUCUUGCCCCUUGACAACAGAAUAAAAAUUUUAGCUGCCCCA